AUAUUGUAUACUGGAAUUGAAGCCAAGGAGGUACCAUUUUGCUCGAGGGCAUGGCCUAAGCCGGUCAGCUAAGGCCAUGUUAAUACGGGGCUGUCCCAUCUCUCUGCGGGGCGCGACAGCUGGAAGAGCCGAACGGAUAAGAGAAGAGGAGGUGAGAGGAGCUGUACACCACAAGAGGCACUGAGGGACUCAGGAUAACGGGAUGAAGCCGUCAGUGCCCCCAGAAACGAAGCGGCCCCGGACGAAUUUCUGAGUCACCGUCGCGAGAAAGCGGGCUGAGCCGCCAUUUUGAAGCCUGGCAAACCGAAGCAAGAAAUGCUGCCGUGUUGGAUCUUUGCCAGCCUUCGUGCCGAAUGGGAGCAGGUUGGAGGGAGGGAGAGCCAAUAUACACUAUGGGCUGAUUAAGCCCGGUUGGCUGCCAUGUUGUUAACGAGCACCGAUUUCCUCUACUUUUGUCGAAGAAGUUUAUUGUGGGUCAGGGACGUCAGGUCGCUUGCCUUCGUUUACUGUGGUCAUGAUUGAGCAUAUGAGGACGGCCAUUAUUGUUGGGGGCAAAUGGAAAUGCUCUAGGCGGGGCCAUUUUUCUUAGGGGCAAGCUGUCGUCACCCUUGUCAACUGGUUCGGAUGAAGCCCCUGUGGCCGCCAUCUUGAUCUCGGGCGGCCCCGAUAAGGGAGGCGGAGUGUGCGGAGAGGAGGCGGGGCAACUGCGCGGACGUGACGCAAGGCGCCGCCAUGUCUUUUGAGGGCGGUGACGGCGCCGGGCCGGCCAUGCUGGCUACGGGCACGGCGCGGAUGGCGUCGGGGCGCCCCGAGGAGCUGUGGGAGGCCGUGGUGGGGGCCGCUGAGCGCUUCCGGGCCCGGACUGGCACGGAGCUGGUGCUGCUGACCGCGGCCCCGCCGCCACCACCCCGCCCGGGCCCCUGUGCCUAUGCUGCCCAUGGUCGAGGAGCCCUGGCGGAGGCAGCGCGCCGUUGCCUCCACGACAUCGCACUGGCCCACAGGGCUGCCACUGCUGCUCGGCCUCCUGCGCCCCCACCAGCACCACAGCCACCCAGUCCCACACCCAGCCCACCCCGGCCUACCCUGGCCAGAGAGGACAACGAGGAGGACGAGGAUGAGCCCACAGAGACAGAGACCUCCGGGGAGCAGCUGGGCAUUAGUGAUAAUGGAGGGCUCUUUGUGAUGGAUGAGGACGCCACCCUCCAGGACCUUCCCCCCUUCUGUGAGUCAGACCCCGAGAGUACAGAUGAUGGCAGCCUGAGCGAGGAGACCCCCGCCGGCCCCCCCACCUGCUCAGUGCCCCCAGCCUCAGCCCUACCCACACAGCAGUACGCCAAGUCCCUGCCUGUGUCUGUGCCCGUCUGGGGCUUCAAGGAGAAGAGGACAGAGGCGCGGUCAUCAGAUGAGGAGAAUGGGCCGCCCUCUUCGCCCGACCUGGACCGCAUCGCGGCGAGCAUGCGCGCGCUGGUGCUGCGAGAGGCCGAGGACACCCAGGUCUUCGGGGACCUGCCACGGCCGCGGCUUAACACCAGCGACUUCCAGAAGCUGAAGCGGAAAUAUUGAAGUCCAGGGAGGGAGCGCCCCGGGCCGCGUCCGCCCCGUCCCACACUACGCCCCCGCCCCACUCCCGGGGCCUGCUAAUCUGAGGCCGAUCCGGGACCGGCCUCCUUGCGUCUCCCAUUCCCAAGAUUGUCCCGCCUCUGCCAAUCCCCGCCGUCCUUCCAGCCCACGACCUGCCGCGCCGAGGAGCGGCAUCUGUCCCGUUUCCCGAUUGGGUCUGUCGUCUCUCUCCGCCUAGCGACAGAUUCCUUCUAUUAAGGGAUUGGCUCGCUGAGUUCUAAGCUCUAAAUGGGUCAACUCCUUUGUUUUCCGCCUAGCGACAAGGGAUUUGCUCGCACGGCAUUGGCUCCAUCCCCUAGUCGCUGGACAGCUCUUUUUUUGAUUGGCUCAAAUCCUGUAAAGGGCUUGACCAGUCUCUACAUAGUCACCGUCCGCUUUUCCUGAGUUCUCCCUCCCAAUUGGCUCCAGCUUCCUGGGGGCGUGGCCAAGCCCUCCUCUUCCCAGAAUUGGCCCGGGGCCUUCAAUUUACGUUCUUUACACUACGGGGACUGGGGUCGUCUUUGCCCACGUCCCGACAACUUGUUCCCUGACCCCCUCAGGGAUGGCCCCAAACUGUCCCUGCCUCUGGCACCCCCUUUCAUUGGUUCCAUCCAUCCCCACAACAGCCUGCCAAUCGAAGCCCGUCCCUGCAUCCAGGAUGGUACCAGCUCCCGCCCCUCGCCCCCCACCUCCACAGGUGCCUUAAAGGGCCCUCGUCCACCCAAGGUGGGGGGCAGGGGCCCUCACUCUCCGGCCCUGGUGUGGGGGAGAGAGUGAGGGGUUGGGGGAUCGGCAGUUGGGAGGGGCGCUCUGAGAUUAAAGAGUUUUACCUCUGAGAUAAAUGUGAA